GAGACAGGUGGGGUACUCGGGAAGCUGGAGCGGGCCGGCGGUGCAGUCACGGGGGAGCGAGGCCUGCUGGGCUUGGCAACGAGGGACUCGGCCUCGGAGGCGACCCAGACCACACAGACACUGGGUCAAGGAGUAAGCAGAGGAUAAACAACUGGAAGGAGAGCAAGCACAAAGUCAUCAUGGCUUCAGCGUCUGCUCGUGGAAACCAAGAUAAAGAUGCCCAUUUUCCACCACCAAGCAAGCAGAGCCUGUUGUUUUGUCCAAAAUCAAAACUGCACAUCCACAGAGCAGAGAUCUCAAAGAUUAUGCGAGAAUGUCAGGAAGAAAGUUUCUGGAAGAGAGCUCUGCCUUUUUCUCUUGUAAGCAUGCUUGUCACCCAGGGACUAGUCUACCAAGGUUAUUUGGCAGCUAAUUCUAGAUUUGGAUCAUUGCCCAAAGUUGCACUUGCUGGUCUCUUGGGAUUUGGCCUUGGAAAGGUAUCAUACAUAGGAGUAUGCCAGAGUAAAUUCCAUUUUUUUGAAGAUCAGCUCCGUGGGGCUGGUUUUGGUCCACAGCAUAACAGGCACUGCCUCCUUACCUGUGAGGAAUGCAAAAUAAAGCAUGGAUUAAGUGAGAAGGGAGACUCUCAGCCUUCAGCUUCCUAAAUUCUGUGUCUGUGACUUUCGAAGUUUUUUAAACCUCUGAAUUUGUACACAUUUAAAAUUUCAAGUGUACUUUAAAAUAAAAUACUUCUAAUGGAACAAAAACAUUGUGUCUGUCACUCACUGAAAUGUAUUCCGUGGAAGGCUUUCAAGUGAACUAAGCGUUACAUGUUUUUCUGCUCUUUAAGAACAUGUCGGGGCAUGGCGCAGUGGCUCAUGCCUGUAAUCCCAGUACUUUGGGAGGCCGAGGCAGGCAGAUCAUUUGAGGUCAGGAGUUCAUGACCAGCUUGGCCAACAUGGUGAAACCCCAUCUCUGCUAAAAAUAUAAAAAUUAGCCAGGCGUGGUGGCACAUGCCUGUAAUCCCAGCUACUGAGAGGGAGGCUGAGGCAGGAGAAUCACUUGAACCCAGGAGGCGAAAGUUGCAGCGAGCAGAGAUUGUGCCACUGCACUCCAGCCUGGGUGCCAGA